AUUAUCCUCCUUAUUGACAAACAGAGCGGUCGCGGCGGCGACUCUCGGCGUGCGGUGAUAGCCAAGCCAUGGGAGACAAGAAGAGCCCCACCAGGCCGAAGCGGCAGCCGAAGCCGUCCUCGGAUGAGGGUUACUGGGACUGUAGCGUCUGCACCUUCCGGAACAGCGCCGAGGCCUUCAAGUGCAUGAUGUGCGAUGUGCGGAAGGGCACCUCCACCCGGGACAGCAAGGAAGGGGGGAAGCUGGUGUCCUACUCCACAGCCAGUCUUGGGGUUAGAGGAACCCUGAGAAAUAGAGUAGGUGGUGGCAGCUCAGAAGAGAAGAAACAGGCUGAAUACCUGGCACCUGGAAGAAGAAGGAAUAUAGUACACAGGGGAGUUGGCCCAGGACAGAGAAGUGGGCCUAGUUUAAAAGAGGCUUGAGGCCCACAUGGGGGCCCCUGACAUUUUUUUUUUUUACCAGUACAUCUAAGCUCUUGUAGAUCCAAUUUUUAGUGGUGGAAACAUUACUUGAGGAGGACUCAGAGAAGCAUUGUCAUUUGGAUUGAAACUGAAGAGGCUCUGGGCAACUCACCAGAAAUCUAAGGGACACUGUGUUCCUGAAAGUAAGUGUUCUACACCACGACCCUCUCAGCUUCUUCCUUCCUCUCUCUGAAUUCUCUUCUCUUUUGAUUUUGGCUCUAAGUUAAACCUAAGAGCUCUAAUUUCUCUGUUAUCUGUUAUUUUCCUAGUGGUUUCUGAAAUUCAGGGUAGAAUCUGUGUUUGUAUAGAACAGUGUGGAACAGGGUAUUGUUACUAGAGAAGAUAUUGAUUGCAUCACAGAAUAUUAAUAUUUUUCCUCUCUGGUAAUGUUAAAAAAACAAGAUUAAAGGACUGCAGAACGGUGUUGAGAAGCAAAAGUUUCAGUAGUUGGAAGAAAUAAUUCUCCAUAAUUGACUUAUUAAUGAACAGGGUAAUUUCCAGAGUAAGGUUGGCAAGUACUAAAGCCAAGACUGGAUAGCUGCAGAGCAGAAGGAUGCAGUUUGCUAAUGAUUUGUUUGUGUGACGCACAGAUGGGAUUUGAAUCCUUUGGGUCAGACUGACCUUUGAACUGAUUCUGCCUCAUUGCCAAAUGUUAGGCCAAGUCUAAGCCAUUCUAGACAUUUGAAAAACUUUUUUCUUUUUAGACCUGCAGAGAAGAUUGAGUCCUUGUUCUACCUUUGAAGUCUUCUUUUUUUCUUUUUUCUUUUUUGAGAUAAGAUCUCAUUCUGUUGCCCAGGCUGGGUUGCAGUGGCAUCAUCCAGGCUCACUGCAGCCUCGAACUCCCAGGUUCAAGGAAUCCUCCCACCUCAGCCUCCCAAGUAGCUGAAACUACAGAUGCACACCACCAUGUGUGGCUAAUUUUCUUAUUUUUUGUAGAGAUGGGGGAUCUCUAUGUUGCCUAGGCUAGUCUCAAACUCUUGAGCUCAAGUGAUCCUCCUACCUUGGCCUCCCAAAGAACUGGGAUUAUAGGAAUGAGCCACCAUUCGGCCCCUUUAAAGUCUUUAUUGGCAAUAUAAUUUUUUUUCUUUAAAUAAUAUUAAGUUCAAAUUCUUUAUGCAACAGAAGCCCAUUUCCUUUGGCUAUAUCCAUGGUAGGUCAUGUCUUUCUAGAGAACGAAGUUACAUUCAUGGCAUGUAUUUCAAAAUAAAAUGAUUUGUUGUAGCUUCAGUUCCUCAAGUUUUAAUUUUAUUUUAGAUUUUGGGGUACAUGUGCAUGUUUGUUACUUGGGUAUAUUGCAGAGUGGUGGGAUUGGGAUUCCAGUGUACCCAUUACCCAAAUGGUGAACGUUAUACCCAACAGGUCAUUUUUCAGCCCCUCACUCCAAAAUUUUUUACAUUGUGCUUUUGUGAGAGAAACAGUAGUAAAUGUCAAACUGACAGGAAAUUUUUUAAAAGGAAACAAAAUGCCACGGUGACACAUUAUUUUCAAGAUGCUGCACAGUCUUUAUAUCUGAAGUUUCUUUUCUUUCUUUUCUUUUCUUUUCUUUUCUUUUCUUUUCUUUUCUCUUUUUUUUUUUGAGGCAGAAUUUGAGACAGUCUUGCUCUGUCGCCCAGGCUGGAGUACAGUGGCGUGACCUCGGCUCACUGCAACCUCCACCUCCCAGGUUCAAGCAAUUCUCAUGCCUCAGCCUCUGUGGUAGCUGGGAUUACAGGUGCCCGCCACCACACCAGGCUAAUUUUUGUAUUUUUAGUAGAGAUGGGGUUUCACUAUGCUGGCCAGGCUGGUCUCAAACUCCUGACCUCAGGUGAUCCGUCUGCGUCGGCUUCCCAAAGUGCUGGGAUUACAGGAGUGAGACACUGUGCCCAGCCUAUCUGAAGAUUCUUAUAAGGCAAGAAAUGUCCCAAAUAUAAAUGCAAGAAACUUUAGGAAAUUAAGGAUCAUUCUUGGCUGGCCCAGUGGCCCACACCUGUAAGCCCAGCACCUUGGGAGGCUGAGACAGGAGGAUUUCUUGAGGCCAGGAGUUUGAGACCAACCUGGGCAACACAGUGAGAUCUCGUCUCUACUAAAAAUUAAAAAAAUUAGCUGGGUGUGGUGGUGCAUGCCUGUGGUCCCAGCUACUCAGGAGGCUGAAGUGGGAGGAUCCCUUGAGCCCCAGAGUUCGAGGUUGCAGUGAGCUGUGAUCAUACCACUGCACUCCAGCCUGGGCAACAGAGUGAGACCUUGUCUCAAAAAAACAAAAUUCUGAGUCAUCAGAGAAAAUGAAAUAUUAAAUAUUAAGGAUAGUCUGUAUGAGGGUGAUAAUCAAUGUGUGAUGAUUAAUUUAAGACUGGUGUCUUAUUGGUACUUCAUCUAGUAGUGGACAGUUACUUAAUAUUGCUUAAUUCAGAUAGCAAAUAUUUAGAAAUGAAAAUGAUAGAAUUAUUGGUUUGGGUUUCAAACUGUGGUCUAAAUGGUUCAUACCAGGCUUUCAAAUGUAACAGGUAAUGUUACAUUUUGUUAGAGGAUAUUAUAACAGUCCUUUAGGUUUCUCAUAGGUGUUAUUUUAGAGAGCUAUAAAAAAGAUUUCACAUAGUAGAAAGAGUGCUAGAUGUUACACUAGUAUGAUUUUGGUAACCUGGGUUCAUAUCUCAUUUCAUAUCAACCAUUUCAAUAUUCAGCAUUCAGCAAAUGUUUAUUGAGCAUCUUAUUUAAGGGCUGAGUUGGAUACUAGACAUACAGUGGUGAGCAAAAUGGAUUUUUUUGUUUCUUUAAAAUUUUACAGUUUUGCAAAUUAGAACCGCUUUAACUGUACCAAGCUCUAUAUGUGAGGUUUAGUGUUAGUAGAUCUUUCCUUUAUGUGUAGGCUGAAGAGGUGGAACUUCUUCAUUAAAAAUAUAUGUUGUUUAUAACUGAACACAGUAUUAUUAUUAUGGUUAGGUAAAAAGAGUGAGUUAUUUCAGCUUCUUUUAAAAGUAAGCUAUAAAAUCCACAUUCUGAAAGAAGCUUAAACCAACUAUCAUCUGGUAGAAAUCUUUUCAGCAUCGUUGUUUUCUUGUCAUACUUGCUUUAUGUCUUCAAAUUUGAGGUUUGGCACUGAUUCUUCUAGACUUUUGGUGUAGGAAUGGGAGAAAAAAAUUGAGGACCAUCUACAUAAGUCCUUUUUAAAGAAAUGCAUGGUUCCUGAGCCGCCUCCUGUCUAUCUGAGGAGCCUUUCUAGCAACCAUUUAGUUGUUCAGAGACUCCUUAUUCUAGGAGAUUUCUUACUUGUUUGUUUUUUGUCCUGUAAGAGGACUCACACUGGUUAAUUGUAUAUGGGUAAAUUUUACAAGUGAUUAUUAGUGUUUGUGUAGUCUGGAUAUCAGAGUGGUUUUCAAAGUGUAGUCUGAGGGACACUGAGAGUCCCUGAGAUCUUUUUAGUUGAAGCUUUCUAUGAGGUUCACACUGUUUUUAUAAUAAUUUGAAGAUGUUAUUUGCCUUUUUCACUGUGAUGGUGCAGAGGCAGUGAUGGGUAAAACUGCCAGCACCUUAGCAUGAAUCAAAGCAGUGGCACCAAAUUGCUAUCUUCAUUGUAAUAUUCACCACCAUGUACAUGCAUGCAGUAAGAAUAAUGUCAGUUUGAAUUAAGAAUAUCCUUGAAGCAGAAAAAUUUACUAAUUUUAUUACAUCUCAUAUUUUUAAAAAUAUUCUGUCUGACCAAAUGGGAACUACACAUAAAGCACUUCUACUGUAUACCAAAGUACAGUGGUUAAGGGAAAGCACAUGUGUAGUUUGUCUUGCAAGCAGAGCUAGUCUUUUUGUCAUAGAGCAUCAUUUUUACUUGAAAGACUACCUGAAAUACCAUAGUUAUUCAGACUUGGAUAUUUAGCAUAUAUUUUCUUGAAAAUGAAUAUAUUCAAAAAAUAUAUCACUUCAAGGAAAACACUUGAUACUAUAUGUUGCCAGUGAUAAUCAUUCAAGUGAAAAUUAGAAUUUUUGAAAAUUUGUAGCAACAAUGAGCUUUAGAGUUUCUGUGUAUAAAGACUUUUCUGAGAAGAUUAGUGGUGGUAUCAAUGAAUAUAAUUUCUGAUAUUUCACCAUGAAAUGUGUCAGCAUUUGGAAGCUACGCAUAACUCAGCAAACAAAUGGUUCCUAGUUACCGAUGUAUGAUUUUACAAAACUGUAAUGGGUAAUCCAUCAAAGUACAAAAUACCAACAGAUUUUAAGGGAACACUGAAAACUUCAUUGAUGUGGUUUCAGAUUUCAUAUUGCAACUAACCUUUGAGAAACAACUGUGUUUUUAUGUAGUAUCAAAGAAUAACACCUAUAGUUAUCUGAAAAUGCUAUUCAACUACUUACCUCUUUUCAACUGUAUAUCUGUGAGAGUCCAGAUUUUCUUAAUAUUUUUGGACCAAAACAACAUAUUGCAACAAAUUGAAUGCUGAGAUAGAUGUGACAAUCCAGGUGUCUUCUACUAACCAGAUGUUAGAGGUUUGCAAAAAUAUACGAUGCCACUCUUCAUACAAAAUAUCUUUGUUUUGGAAAAUAAUAAGUUUUUAAAAUAAAAAUAUGUCAUUUAA